GCCCCGGGGUAAGCUCGCGCCGCCGCGUCAGCUCAGCGCUGGGUCUCUCGGUCCCGCAGCCGUGAGGAGGACGGUCUGCAUACUCGCUGCCCGCCGGCUCCCUCCCCCGCGUCCCUGCGACCGCCGCGGCGAAGAUGAUUUUCAGUUCACCCACUAGAGGCAAAGACGUAAGAGAGCUACCAGCGUAUUGAGAGGAGAUACACAGGCACUACGAGAAUGGAGUUUAGAAGAAGGUCAGAGCCCUGGGCAGUGUUGGGCCAGGCUUUAGGGCCUCAGGAGUGCAAGUAGCUGAUGAAGUAUGUCGCAUUUUUUAUGACAUGAAAGUUCGUAAAUGCUCCACACCAGAAGAAAUCAAGAAAAGAAAGAAGGCUGUCAUUUUUUGUCUCAGUGCAGACAAAAAGUGCAUCAUUGUAGAAGAAGGCAAAGAGAUCUUGGUUGGAGAUGUUGGUGUAACCAUAACUGAUCCUUUCAAGCAUUUUGUGGGAAUGCUUCCUGAAAAAGAUUGUCGCUAUGCUUUGUAUGAUGCAAGCUUUGAAACAAAAGAAUCCAGAAAAGAAGAGUUGAUGUUUUUUUUGUGGGCACCAGAACUAGCACCUCUGAAAAGUAAAAUGAUCUAUGCAAGCUCCAAGGAUGCAAUUAAAAAGAAAUUUCAAGGCAUAAAACAUGAAUGUCAAGCAAAUGGACCAGAAGAUCUCAAUCGGGCUUGUAUUGCUGAAAAGUUAGGUGGAUCCUUAAUUGUAGCCUUUGAAGGAUGCCCUGUGUAGAUUAUUCAGUGCCACAAAUUGAAAGCUUCCAUGUUUAAUGUUAUCCUCUUGCUAUAUAAAUAAAGCAAAUAUAUUUAGGCCAGGGUCUCACUGAGGGGGAGCUGUCUUGUCAUCUUUUAGAGUAAACUAUUCUAUAAACAUAUGCAAACAGCCCUAAAUAAAUCUAAAGUCUAAAGUUUUAUUGAUGUGAAAUUAAAUUCUUAUUGGCCAAAUGCCUGUUUUGAUGAGUUGAUUUAUAAAGAUUUUUGUUAAGCUCAGGAUUUUAAAUUACACAGUUCACAAACAGUAAAGGCCAUGUGAAGAGAAUUAUUACAUCUUUAUUAACCUCAGCAUUUACUUUGUUUCUUUUGCUUAGGAAAUUGCUCAUAAUCUGGUUAUAAUUUUGGUCCAAAUUCUUUAUUCUUCCUUGAGCUAAGCAGAAUAAUGGAAUAUAAUAUGUCUUCAUAAUAUAACAACACUAAUACACUAAUAGUAAGAUUAAGUUAGGCAGUCUUCUACCAAAUGUGUAAUGGAGAUUGCCUCAAAAUUGUGUCCACAUAAUCCACGCUCAUCUUGCAAAGCGCUAUUUCAGGCACAUCAUUGGAAUACAGGAAGUAGCCCUGCACCUGCCAGUGAGCUCGCCAUUCACUGAUUGGAAGAGUGACCUGGCAUCUUGGAAAUCAUUGUGUGUCUUCAGGAGAAUGUGCAGUGUCUUGUAACAACUAAUUAUAAUGCAAAUUAGGGCUACAUUGUAAUCUGCUUUGUUAAUGAAAAUGAUAAAACAGAAUAUUGACAAGCUAGGACACCUGUGGUAUCUUUAAUUGUAUCUCCUUCAGAAGUUUGCUUCUUAUGGUAUAAUAAAGUAUGGAAGAAUAUUGAGUAUAUGUUUACUCUGGGCCUGGGAGAACUUAACUUUCUAGAGCAGUUUGUUGACUUGUGUGCAAUGGGGAGAGGUACCAUGAUGACACUCACAGGGAGCCACUGUUCACUGACACUUGGAAGCGGUCAUUGUUAAUAUCACGGGCGUAACACUUUGAACGAUAUAGAGAUGCACAAACAGUUGAACUUAGAAGUAGCAGUAUUGGCUUUAUGUAAUAAAGGAAGCAUUUUUGACUUACCUCUCGUGUAAUUUUCAUGUGUGAAUUGGGAAUACAGGAUUUUGCCUUCCAUAUGGGGUAAGGCAUUGAGGUUUGGGUAUUUCCAAUAAUUAAGAGUUAAGGUUGGCUGAGUGUGGUGGCUCACUCCUGUAAUCCCAGCAUUUUGGGAGGCCGAGGCAAGAGGAUAGUUUGAGGCCAGGAGUUUGACAAUCAGCGUGGGCAACAUAGUGGGAUCUCAUCUACUAAAAAUAAACAAAAUUAGCCGGGUGUGGUGGUGCACGUCAGUAGUCCCAGCUACUUUGGAUGCUGAGGUGGGAGGAUCACUUGAGCCCAGGAGGUGAGCUGAGAUCGUGCCACUGUACUCCAGCCUGGAUGACAGAGCAAGACCUUGUCUCAAAAAAAAAAAAAAAAGUCACAACUCCCUCUGGUGAAUAAGAAAGUUGGUGUAAAAGUUGGGAACGUUUUCAAUGUUUAUUACACUAUAAGUGUAAUAAAUAUUAUACAAAAUUAUAAAUUCACAUUUAAAAUUUAGAAAAUAGAGAAAAGGGAAAUUAUACAUUGUCCUACCACAUGCCAUCACAUGGUUAGCAUUUUGAUACACAGCUGUGCAUUAUUACAUGUCAAAGACUGCAUAUACUAUGGUGGUCCCAUACAAUUAUAAUGUAUUUUCUACUGUAAUUAGAUACACAAAUACCAUUGUGUUACAGUUGCCGACAGUAUUCAGUAUAGUAACGUGCUGUCCAGGUUUGUGGUCUAGGAGUAAUAGGCUCUACCAUACAGCCUAGGUGUGUAGUAGGCUAUGCCACUAGGUUUAAGUGCAGUCUAGGGUGGGGAACAUUUUAAUGUUGAUCCACAUGCCAGGUGUUUGUGAGACAAGAUUAUGCUUUAAUCAAAAUAUUUUGGAAUUGUCUAGAAAAUAGUGCUGGCUGCUUGUCAUUCAUCCUGAAUUGCUUGUUUCUUUACUUUGUAGCAAUGCUUUUAGUGUGGGUUUUGUUUUUUGAGACAGGGUCUCACUCUUUCCCCCAGGCUAGAGUGCAGUGGUGCAAUCAUAACUCACUGCAUCCUUGAACUCUUGGGCUCCAGCAAGCCUCCUGCCUUGGCCUCCUAAAGUGCUGUGAUUACAGGUGUGAGCCACUGUGUCCUGCUAGUGAUUGUGAUUAACAGGCCUCCAGGGAAGUGCCAUAAGCCCAAGACUGCCGUACUCAAAAGUCAGCCAUGUAGGUAAAGCAAGAUAUUUGGUCAAGGAGUUUUAGAAGGAGAUUUUUCCUGUGGUGUUGGCUUAAGUGUGGCACUGUUGUGCGUGUGUGAGGUGUCUUCUGUGGGAAGGAUUUCAAACAGUACAAAGGGAUGUGAUGUAAGCAUCCAGAACUCACUCCAGAAAUUGAAUAAAAUGCUAGUAGUUAGUCUCUAGGGGAACUUUUGAGAAAGUCUCAGUGGAUUCCUGAGGCCCAAGAAUUGUGCUAACAAGCACUCAAGGCGAUUCUGGUACAUAAUUAGGGUUCAGACCUCAGCUGAUUGGUCUACUGUUGGUCAGGAACAAAACUGCAAGUAUACUCUGUUUCCAGAAAAUACGUUUACCUCUUCACAAAUGCUAACACACUGCAAAAAUAUGUUUGUGGAAAGCUGACUUAGUCUCAUCUAGCGGUUACUCUCUUGCCCUGACAAAGCAGCAAAUAAAGCCAUUGCUAACAAUUCAA